CCACAUCCCAGGAGGCCGAGGCGGCUUGCCCCGCAUCUCAGAAGCCGGGCAGGCCCUGAGCCUUCUGACCUCACAUCCUCUGCCACACCACAGUGGAGAAACCAGAACUGGAGGAGCAGCCAGAAUGCAGAGAAGAAAAAAGAGGUUCUCUGCAUGUUUGGAAGUCGGAAUUGGUUGAAGUUGAAGAUGAUGUGUAUCUGAGGCACAGCUCUUCCCUGACUUAUAGGCUUUGACACUGCUGUUGAGGUUUGACUCGAAGCCCAGAGUUUUGGUGUGGAUGAGCAGGGACAAAUUGCUGAGCAUGAAGAAGAGUAAAAUUAAGCAAGUGGAACAUAUGCCCUUUGCCUCUGCUCUGCACAGUGAAAUGAAAAGUCAACCUUU